AUCCUCCUCCAGGUCCUGGCGCACAGGGUGGGAGCGCUGCGCUGCGCCGCGCUGCGCAUCGCGGCCCGCUUGCCGCCUGCCCCCUGCCCUAGCUGGGCCACCUCCCCGGGCUGCCGGUGGAGGGCUAAGAGGCGCUAACGUUACGCUGUUUCCGGUUUUCCAGCGGGCUCUGUUUCCCCUCCCAAGGCGGCGGCGGCUGAGCGGCGGAGCCCCCCAAAUGGCCUGGCCAGAUGCGGCAGGUUUGCUGCUCAGCGCUGCCGCCGCCGCCACUGGAGAAGGGUCGGUGCAGCAGCUACAGCGACAGCAGCAGCAGCAGCAGCGAGAGGAGCAGCAGCAGCAGCAGCAGCAGCAGCGAGAGCGGCAGCAGCAGCAGGAGCAGCAGCAACAACAGCAGCAUCUCUCGUCCCGCUGCGCCCCCAGAGCCGCGGCCGCAGCAACAGCCGCAGCCCCGCAGCCCCGCAGCCCGGAGAGCCGCCGCCCGUUCGCGAGCCGCAGCCGCCGGCGGCAUGAGGCGCGACCCGGCCCCCGGCUUCUCCAUGCUGCUCUUCGGUGUGUCGCUCGCCUGCUACUCGCCCAGCCUCAAGUCAGUGCAGGACCAGGCGUACAAGGCACCCGUGGUGGUGGAGGGCAAGGUACAGGGGCUGGUCCCAGCCGGCGGCUCCAGCUCCAACAGCACCCGAGAGCCGCCCGCCUCGGGUCGGGUGGCGUUGGUAAAGGUGCUGGACAAGUGGCCGCUCCGGAGCGGGGGGCUGCAGCGCGAGCAGGUGAUCAGCGUGGGCUCCUGUGUGCCGCUCGAAAGGAACCAGCGCUACAUCUUUUUCCUGGAGCCCACGGAACAGCCCUUAGUCUUUAAGACGGCCUUUGCCCCCCUCGAUACCAACGGCAAAAAUCUCAAGAAAGAGGUGGGCAAGAUCCUGUGCACUGACUGCGCCACCCGGCCCAAGUUGAAGAAGAUGAAGAGCCAGACGGGACAGGUGGGUGAGAAGCAAUCGCUGAAGUGUGAGGCAGCAGCCGGUAAUCCCCAGCCUUCCUACCGUUGGUUCAAGGAUGGCAAGGAGCUCAACCGCAGCCGAGACAUUCGCAUCAAAUAUGGCAACGGCAGAAAGAACUCACGACUACAGUUCAACAAGGUGAAGGUGGAGGACGCUGGGGAGUAUGUCUGCGAGGCCGAGAACAUCCUGGGGAAGGACACCGUCCGGGGCCGGCUUUACGUCAACAGCGUGAGCACCACCCUGUCAUCCUGGUCGGGGCACGCCCGGAAGUGCAACGAGACAGCCAAGUCCUAUUGCGUCAAUGGAGGCGUCUGCUACUACAUCGAGGGCAUCAACCAGCUCUCCUGCAAAUGUCCAAAUGGAUUCUUCGGACAGAGAUGUUUGGAGAAACUGCCUUUGCGAUUGUACAUGCCAGAUCCUAAGCAAAAGCACCUUGGAUUUGAAUUAAAGGAAGCCGAGGAGCUGUACCAGAAGAGGGUCCUGACCAUCACGGGCAUCUGCGUGGCUCUGCUGGUCGUGGGCAUCGUCUGUGUGGUGGCCUACUGCAAGACCAAAAAACAGCGGAAGCAGAUGCACAACCACCUCCGGCAGAACAUGUGCCCGGCCCAUCAGAACCGGAGCUUGGCCAAUGGGCCCAGCCACCCCCGGCUGGACCCAGAGGAGAUCCAGAUGGCAGAUUAUAUUUCCAAGAACGUGCCAGCCACAGACCAUGUCAUCAGGAGAGAAACUGAGACCACCUUCUCUGGGAGCCACUCCUGUUCUCCUUCUCACCACUGCUCCACAGCCACACCCACCUCCAGCCACAGACACGAGAGCCACACGUGGAGCCUGGAACGUUCUGAGAGCCUGACUUCUGACUCCCAGUCGGGGAUCAUGCUAUCAUCAGUGGGUACCAGCAAAUGCAACAGCCCAGCAUGUGUGGAGGCCCGGGCAAGGCGGGCAGCAGCCUACAACCUGGAGGAGCGGCGCAGGGCCACCGCGCCACCCUAUCACGAUUCCGUGGACUCCCUUCGCGACUCCCCACACAGCGAGAGGUACGUGUCGGCCCUGACCACGCCCGCGCGCCUCUCGCCCGUGGACUUCCACUACUCGCUGGCCACGCAGGUGCCAACUUUCGAGAUCACGUCCCCCAACUCGGCGCACGCCGUGUCGCUGCCGCCGGCGGCGCCCAUCAGUUACCGCCUGGCCGAGCAGCAGCCGUUACUGCGGCACCCGGCGCCCCCCGGCCCGGGACCCGGACCCGGGCCCGGGCCCGGGCCCGGCGCAGACAUGCAGCGCAGCUAUGACAGCUACUAUUACCCCGCGGCGGGGCCCGGACCGCGGCGCGGGACCUGCGCGCUCGGCGGCAGCCUGGGCAGCCUGCCUGCCAGCCCCUUCCGCAUCCCCGAGGACGACGAGUACGAGACCACGCAGGAGUGCGCGCCCCCGCCGCCGCCGCGGCCGCGCGCGCGCGGUGCGUCCCGCAGGACGUCGGCGGGGCCCCGGCGCUGGCGCCGCUCGCGCCUCAACGGGCUGGCGGCGCAGCGCGCACGGGCGGCGAGGGACUCGCUGUCGCUGAGCAGCGGCUCGGGCGGCGGCUCAGCCUCGGCGUCGGACGACGACGCGGACGACGCGGACGGGGCGCUGGCGGCCGAGAGCACACCUUUCCUGGGCCUGCGUGGGGCGCACGACGCGCUGCGCUCGGACUCGCCGCCACUGUGCCCGGCGGCCGACAGCAGGACUUACUACUCACUGGACAGCCACAGCACGCGGGCCAGCAGCAGACACAGCCGCGGGCCGCCCCCGCGGGCCAAGCAGGACUCGGCGCCACUCUAGGGCCCCGCCGCGCGCCCCUCCGCCCCGCCCGCCCCACUAUCUUUAAGGAGACCAGAGACCGCCUACUGGAGAGAAAGGAGGAAAAAAGAAAUAAAAAUAUUUUUAUUUUCUAUAAAAGGAAAAAAGUAUAACAAAAUGUUUUAUUUUCAUUUUAGCAAAAAUUGUCUUAUAAUACUAGCUAACGGCAAAGGCGUUUUUAUAGGGAAACUAUUUAUAUGUAACAUCCUGAUUUACAGCUUCGGAAAAAAAAAAGAAACAACAAAAAAAAAAGAGAGAUGGGCCAAUUUUUUGACUCUUUAAUAGAAACCUAUUUUGUGGUGCCUUUUGCUGUAUGCUCAUCUGGGGCUCCGGGGGACAGGUCUGGGUUGUGGGGUGCUGAGAGUGACAGCUGGGAGAGAAGAGGUGCGGGUUCUGUUGGGGGCGAGGGUGGGGGGCGGUGGGGGGUUGGCCCUAAGGAAGAACUGAGGACGGAAGUAGCUUUGCUCCCAGGCAAGAGCUGAAGUUCCCGACCCCUGGGAGGAGAGGGCCAGGACCCUAGGCUUGGAGCUGGAGCUGGGGUAACUUCCAGGGGGAGAUAAAGACACAGCUACCCGAAUGGGGAAGCCCUGGCUACUCACAGCUGUUAAAGGAGGGGGGGCAGAGAAACGUUUCCCCAAGAGCCUGAGCCCAGGGAGGUGGCAGCUCUGCCAGGGGCCCAAUGUUGGCGGCUCCUGUCCCCCACAGCCUCCAGGACGCCCCUCCGUCCUCUGCAGCACCUUCGUUUACAGGUCGUCUUUUCUAUUUUACACCUGCAUGUCCUUUGCAUUUCAGAUUCUUUAGAUUGGAUGCAUGGUCACGCUGGGACCGAGAAGAGCCACUCGACAGUGUAUUCCCCUUUUAGCAAUAAAGUAACACCAUUUCCUUCUCACAGGCUGCCUCCUAGCCCCCAACCCACCUAUGACAUCCACUCGUCUCCAGUCCUGCCCUCCCACCCCCAAAAACUGGGUCCACUGCUAAUUUGUCAAAAAGGUAAUUGUUUAAAAAAAAAAAAAAUCCCAAACAGAAACAGAUGGGAAUCCUGUCCUGAAAUGUCUGAACACCUGACUGUUGACACUUGAACAUUUUUAUAUUAUAAAUAAAAUCAGAAAUAACUCCUG